ACUUUCCCGAGAGGAGCGCGGGCGCCAGUUGCCUCCUUUUAAAGUUUGAGGGGCGGUGGUGGCGGCGGCCGGCAGGCGCGGGGGAACACAGGGGCCGCUACGGGAGCCGCGCCGCCGCCCAUGUCAUUCCACUUCAAGUGACUUCAUGUGAUGUCAGCUGAAUGUAAAAGACAGUGAUCUCACGCGGAGGGGAAGAUGUUUGCCAUCAAAAUGUGACAGAAGAGACACGCUGCAUGGCUCGGAACGCAUCUCCUUGGUGGUGGGGGAAAGAGACUUAGAGGAGAGAGGCUGCGCCCUGGCCCAGCCUGGCUCGGCUCAGCUCCGCGCGCCAUGGCAAGCUCGGCUUCCCUGGAGACCAUGGUGCCCCCGGCCUGCCCGCGCGCCGGAGCGUCGCCGGCCACUUCCAAGACACUGGCCUUUUCCAUCGAGCGCAUCAUGGCCAAGACGUCGGAGCCCCGUGCGCCCUUUGAGCCCCGGCCUGGAGCGCUAGAGGCGGACGGCAGCCAGGGCAAGAAACUGCUCAACCUCUGCUCGCCGCUGCCCUGUAUGAUCCCCCUCCAGCCCCUAGGCUACGAGGUGCCGUCAAAGACACUGCUCAGUUACUCGGAGCUCUGGAAAAGCAGCCUCCGGGCGGGCGGCGGCGGAGGCGGCGGCGGCGGUGGCGGCGGCGGCGGCGGGGGGGCCCCAGUGUGCGGCGCCAGCGGCUUGUGCAAAACCAACUGUGGCGUGUGCUGCAAGGCCGAGCUGGGCCUGGCGCCGUCCGCGCUGCCCGCGGGCAGGGUCAUCAAGCCGCAGGUCAUCAACCAGGCUGUGGGGCUGCCGGCCAGCGGCUCGCUCUACUACUUCAACUACCUGGACUCGACCGCGUACCCGCCGUCUGAGCUCCUCAGCGGCCACCUCUUCCCGUCUGGCCUCCUCAAUGCGCAGGCCCCCGCCGCCCUGGCUGCUCACCCCAAGCUCUUUCUGCUGGAGAACGCCAAGCUGGCCGGCCUGGCUGCGGACAAGUUCCCCCACCCGGCUCCCUAUCCCCAUAAGGAGCGCUUGCCGGCGCCGCUGGAGCAGGUACUGAAGGAAAACUCGGCCCUGACUGCCGAGCGCGGAGGCGUCAAGGGCCACAGCAAGCUGCCAGGAGGCUCCGCAGAUGGCAAGCCCAAAAACUUCACCUGCGAGGUGUGCGGCAAGGUGUUUAACGCUCACUAUAAUCUCACCCGCCACAUGCCGGUCCACACCGGAGCCAGACCGUUCGUGUGCAAAGUCUGCGGCAAAGGCUUUCGCCAGGCCAGCACGCUCUGCAGGCACAAAAUUAUCCACACCCAGGAAAAGCCACAUAAAUGCAACCAGUGCGGCAAAGCGUUCAACCGCAGCUCCACGCUCAACACGCAUAUCCGCAUCCACGCGGGCUACAAGCCCUUCGUCUGCGAAUUUUGCGGCAAAGGCUUUCACCAAAAAGGGAACUACAAGAACCACAAGCUGACCCACAGCGGCGAGAAGCAGUACAAAUGUACCAUCUGCAACAAGGCCUUCCACCAGGUCUACAACCUAACCUUCCAUAUGCACACCCACAACGACAAGAAGCCUUUCACGUGCGCCACUUGCGGCAAAGGGUUUUGCAGAAACUUUGACUUAAAGAAACAUGUGCGCAAACUCCACGACAGCGUGGGCCCUGCUGCCCCCUCCGCAAAGGACCUGACUAGGACAGUGCAGAGCUGAGAGCUACUGCCUUGCCCUUCCUUCCCUCCCUGUACCACCUGAAAACAGAUCACACAUAUAAACUUAUUUCUAAAAUUAAAAGAAAAAAAAACUAUAGCAGAGAGGCUAAAAUCUAUUUAUCGAAACCAGCAUAUUUUUGGAAAGCUAAAUGUUUCCUCGAUGACUGGCAGCAAACUCGUGGCCCCCACCUUUGUAUAUUCAGGAAACUUAUUUAAAUCCAGUGCGCCGAAACGUAUUUAAUUCCAGGCCUCCGCUUCUCCUGGGGCAGCCAGUUUUAACCCCAGCCUGUCACCGUGAGCGCCCCAGAAGAGCGCGGCGCCCCUAGCCAUCUUUAUACAGCCAUGUAAAUCCUCCUGUACAAGCGAACACGGAAUAUAUACAUAUAUAACUCAAUAAACAGAA